CUUCGGAUUUUCUACAGUAGAAUUAUGUCAUCUGCAAAUGAAGAUAGUUUUACUUCUUUCUUUUCAGUGUGGAUGCCUUUAAUGUCUUUUUCUUAACUUAUUGCACAAAUUGCGCAUUCAGUAGUACAAUGUUUAGUGGGACCAGUGAGAAAAGACAUCCUUGCCUUGUUUUGAUCUUAGGGAGGAAAGUCUUUGGUCUCACUGUUAAGUGUGAUAUUAGCUGUACGUUUUGCGUAAGGGCUGUAUUCGUUUGCUAGGACUGCCAUACAAGGUACCACACACUGGGUGGCUUAAAAAACAGAAUGUAUUUUCUCAGAGUUCUGGAGGCAUAAAGGCCAGGAUCAAGGUGCCGGGGGGUUGGUUCCCUCUGAGGACCUCUUUCCUUGGCUUGUCUACAGCCGCCUUCUCCCUAUGUCUUCACAGGAUCUUCCCUCUGUGUGUCUCUUCUUAUAACGAGGCCAGUCAGACUGGAUCAGGACCCACCCCAGUGACCUCAUUUAACUUUAAUUACCUCUUUAAAGACCCUAUCUCUAAAUACAGUGACACGGAGGUAAUGGAGACCAUCAACAAGAUUUCAAGGCUUUAAAGAAAGGAGCUGCUUCAGGAAGAGAUAAAAUGACUCGAACGCUAUAACCUUCAAAUGCAGACUGGGAGAAGAGCCCAGCCUGACUCCUGGAGAUUGUGAAUAGCUCCAUCCAGCCUGAGAAACAAGCCGGGUGGCUGAGCCAGGCUGUGCACGGAGCGCCUGACGGGCCCAACAGACCCAUGCUGCAUCCAGAGACCUCCCCUGGCCGGGGGCAUCUCCUGGCUGUGCUCCUGGCCCUCCUUGGCACCGCCUGGGCAGAGGUGUGGCCACCCCAGCUGCAGGAGCAGGCUCCGAUGGCCGGAGCCCUGAACAGGAAGGAGAGUUUCUUGCUCCUCUCCCUGCACAACCGCCUGCGCAGCUGGGUCCAGCCCCCUGCGGCUGACAUGCGGAGGCUGGACUGGAGUGACAGCCUGGCCCAGCUGGCUCAAGCCAGGGCAGCCCUCUGUGGAACCCCAACCCCGAGCCUGGCGUCCGGCCUGUGGCGCACCCUGCAAGUGGGCUGGAACAUGCAGCUGCUACCCGCGGGCUUGGUGUCCUUUGUCGAAGUGGUCAGCCUAUGGUUUGCAGAGGGGCAGCGGUACAGCCACGCGGCAGGAGAGUGUGCUCGCAACGCCACCUGCACCCACUACACGCAGCUCGUGUGGGCCACCUCAAGCCAGCUGGGCUGUGGGCGGCACCUGUGCUCUGCAGGCCAGGCAGCGAUAGAAGCCUUUGUCUGUGCCUACUCCCCCAGAGGCAACUGGGAGGUCAACGGGAAGACAAUCGUCCCCUAUAAGAAGGGUGCCUGGUGUUCGCUCUGCACAGCCAGUGUCUCAGGCUGCUUCAAAGCCUGGGACCAUGCAGGGGGGCUCUGUGAGGUCCCCAGGAAUCCUUGUCGCAUGAGCUGCCAGAACCAUGGACGUCUCAACAUCAGCACCUGCCACUGCCACUGUCCCCCUGGCUACACGGGCAGAUACUGCCAAGUGAGGUGCAGCCUGCAGUGUGUGCACGGCCGGUUCCGGGAGGAGGAGUGCUCGUGCGUCUGUGACAUCGGCUACGGGGGAGCCCAGUGUGCCACCAAGGUGCAUUUUCCCUUCCACACCUGUGACCUGAGGAUCGACGGAGACUGCUUCAUGGUGUCUUCAGAGGCAGACACCUAUUACAGAGCCAGGAUGAAAUGUCAGAGGAAAGGCGGGGUGCUGGCCCAGAUCAAGAGCCAGAAAGUGCAGGACAUCCUCGCCUUCUAUCUGGGCCGCCUGGAGACCACCAACGAGGUGAUUGACAGUGACUUCGAGACCAGGAACUUCUGGAUCGGGCUCACCUACAAGACCGCCAAGGACUCCUUCCGCUGGGCCACAGGGGAGCACCAGGCCUUCACCAGUUUUGCCUUUGGGCAGCCUGACAACCACGGGUUUGGCAACUGCGUGGAGCUGCAGGCUUCAGCUGCCUUCAACUGGAACGACCAGCGCUGCAAAACCCGAAACCGUUACAUCUGCCAGUUUGGCUCUCCUUCUGCCUCCGCAUGCCCAACGAUCCGGAGAAAAACACGGACCAUGACAUCAAAAGGCCUUGGCAAAGGAAUCGUGAUUAUUGUGAUACAAGAUUCUGCACCUCAAAGGGGAUCCCUGUAGUGAGUUUUGGAAAACGUACAAAGCCUGACUUACAGUAUGCCUGUUAUCUGUGGCGUUUCAUCUGGGGAACUUACUUUUCCUUGAUAGGGUAAACUAUUCUCAUCCAGAGUAUGUCCCUCAGUCUGUAAAAGUCCAUGGUGCCCUACAUCUAUUAGGGGAGUGAGGAAGGGCAGUGGACAUUGGAUCUGCUUCUUUGAAAGCCCCCACUUGUGUUUAGCUUCUGUUAGAGGCCUUUGAACCAGAGCAACUCCAUCUUGAGUAGGCGCUGGGUAAAAUGAGGCUGAGACCUACUGGGCUGUGUUCCCAGGCGGUUGAGGCAUUCUAAGUCACAGGAUGAGAUGAGAGGCCGGCACAAGCAGUAAAGAAGCCGCGGCCAAAACCCACCAAAACCAAGAUGGUGAUGCGAAUGACCUCUGGUCGUCCUCACUGCUACACUCCCACCAGCGCCAAGACAGCUUACAAAUGCCAUGGCAACGCCAGAAUGUUACCCUAUAUGGUCUAAAAAUGGGAGGCAUGAAUAAUCCACCCCUUCUUUAGCAUAUAAUCAAUAAAUAACCAUAAAAAUGA